AAAGGGGCAAGAGCUGAGCGGAACACCGGCCCGCCGUCGCGGCAGCUGCUUCACCCCUCUCUCUGCAGCCAUGGGGCUCCCUCGUGGACCUCUCGCGUCUCUCCUCCUUCUCCAGGUUUGCUGGCUGCAGUGCGCGGCCUCCGAGCCGUGCCGGGCGGUCUUCAGGGAGGCUGAAGUGACCUUGGAGGCGGGAGGCGCGGAGCAGGAGCCCGGCCAGGCGCUGGGGAAAGUAUUCAUGGGCUGCCCUGGGCAAGAGCCAGCUCUGUUUAGCACUGAUAAUGAUGACUUCACUGUGCGGAAUGGCGAGACAGUCCAGGAAAGAAGGUCACUGAAGGAAAGGAAUCCAUUGAAGAUCUUCCCAUCCAAACGUAUCUUACGAAGACACAAGAGAGAUUGGGUGGUUGCUCCAAUAUCUGUCCCUGAAAAUGGCAAGGGUCCCUUCCCCCAGAGACUGAAUCAGCUCAAGUCUAAUAAAGAUAGAGACACCAAGAUUUUCUACAGCAUCACGGGGCCGGGGGCAGACAGCCCCCCUGAGGGUGUCUUCGCUGUAGAGAAGGAGACAGGCUGGUUGUUGUUGAAUAAGCCACUGGACCGGGAGGAGAUUGCCAAGUAUGAGCUCUUUGGCCACGCUGUGUCAGAGAAUGGUGCCUCAGUGGAGGACCCCAUGAACAUCUCCAUCAUCGUGACCGACCAGAAUGACCACAAGCCCAAGUUUACCCAGGACACCUUCCGAGGGAGUGUCUUAGAGGGAGUCCUACCAGGUACUUCUGUGAUGCAGGUGACAGCCACGGAUGAGGAUGAUGCCAUCUACACCUACAAUGGGGUGGUUGCUUACUCCAUCCAUAGCCAAGAACCAAAGGACCCACACGACCUCAUGUUCACCAUUCACCGGAGCACAGGCACCAUCAGCGUCAUCUCCAGUGGCCUGGACCGGGAAAAAGUCCCUGAGUACACACUGACCAUCCAGGCCACAGACAUGGAUGGGGACGGCUCCACCACCACGGCAGUGGCAGUAGUGGAGAUCCUUGAUGCCAAUGACAAUGCUCCCAUGUUUGACCCCCAGAAGUACGAGGCCCAUGUGCCUGAGAAUGCAGUGGGCCAUGAGGUGCAGAGGCUGACGGUCACUGAUCUGGACGCCCCCAACUCACCAGCGUGGCGUGCCACCUACCUUAUCAUGGGCGGUGACGACGGGGACCAUUUUACCAUCACCACCCACCCUGAGAGCAACCAGGGCAUCCUGACAACCAGGAAGGGUUUGGAUUUUGAGGCCAAAAACCAGCACACCCUGUACGUUGAAGUGACCAACGAGGCCCCUUUUGUGCUGAAGCUCCCAACCUCCACAGCCACCAUAGUGGUCCACGUGGAGGAUGUGAAUGAGGCACCUGUGUUUGUCCCACCCUCCAAAGUCGUUGAGGUCCAGGAGGGCAUCCCCACUGGGGAGCCUGUGUGUGUCUACACUGCAGAAGACCCUGACAAGGAGAAUCAAAAGAUCAGCUACCGCAUCCUGAGAGACCCAGCAGGGUGGCUAGCCAUGGACCCAGACAGUGGGCAGGUCACAGCUGUGGGCACCCUCGACCGUGAGGAUGAGCAGUUUGUGAGGAACAACAUCUAUGAAGUCAUGGUCUUGGCCAUGGACAAUGGAAGCCCUCCCACCACUGGCACGGGAACCCUUCUGCUAACACUGAUUGAUGUCAAUGACCAUGGCCCAGUCCCUGAGCCCCGUCAGAUCACCAUCUGCAACCAAAGCCCUGUGCGCCAGGUGCUGAACAUCACGGACAAGGACCUGUCUCCCCACACCUCCCCUUUCCAGGCCCAGCUCACAGAUGACUCAGACAUCUACUGGACGGCAGAGGUCAACGAGGAAGGUGACACAGUGGUCUUGUCCCUGAAGAAGUUCCUGAAGCAGGAUACAUAUGACGUGCACCUUUCUCUGUCUGACCAUGGCAACAAAGAGCAGCUGACGGUGAUCAGGGCCACUGUGUGCGACUGCCAUGGCCAUGUCGAAACCUGCCCUGGACCCUGGAAGGGAGGUUUCAUCCUCCCUGUGCUGGGGGCUGUCCUGGCUCUGCUGUUCCUCCUGCUGGUGCUGCUUUUGUUGGUGAGAAAGAAGCGGAAGAUCAAGGAGCCCCUCCUACUCCCAGAAGAUGACACCCGUGACAACGUCUUCUACUAUGGCGAAGAGGGGGGUGGCGAAGAGGACCAGGACUAUGACAUCACCCAGCUCCACCGAGGUCUGGAGGCCAGGCCGGAGGUGGUUCUCCGCAAUGACGUGGCACCAACCAUCAUCCCGACACCCAUGUACCGUCCUCGGCCAGCCAACCCAGAUGAAAUCGGCAACUUUAUAAUUGAGAACCUGAAGGCGGCUAACACAGACCCCACAGCCCCGCCCUACGACACCCUCUUGGUGUUCGACUAUGAGGGCAGCGGCUCCGACGCCGCGUCCCUGAGCUCCCUCACCUCCUCCGCCUCCGACCAAGACCAAGAUUACGAUUAUCUGAACGAGUGGGGCAGCCGCUUCAAGAAGCUGGCAGACAUGUACGGUGGCGGGGAGGACGACUAGGCGGCCUGCCUGCAGGGCUGGGGACCAAACGUCAGGCCACAGAGCAUCUCCAAGGGGUCUCAGUUCCCCCUUCAGCUGAGGACUUCGGAGCUUGUCAGGAAGUGGCCGUAGCAACUUGGCGGAGACAGGCUAUGAGUCUGACGUUAGAGUGGUGGCUUCCUUAGCCUUUCAGGAUGGAGGAAUGUGGGCAGUUUGACUUCAGCACUGAAAACCUCUCCACCUGGGCCAGGGUUGCCUCAGAGGCCAAGUUUCCAGAAGCCUCUUACCUGCCGUAAAAUGCUCAACCCUGUGUCCUGGGCCUGGGCCUGCUGUGACUGACCUACAGUGGACUUUCUCUCUGGAAUGGAACCUUCUUAGGCCUCCUGGUGCAACUUAAUUUUUUUUUUUAAUGCUAUCUUCAAAACGUUAGAGAAAGUUCUUCAAAAGUGCAGCCCAGAGCUGCUGGGCCCACUGGCCGUCCUGCAUUUCUGGUUUCCAGACCCCAAUGCCUCCCAUUCGGAUGGAUCUCUGCGUUUUUAUACUGAGUGUGCCUAGGUUGCCCCUUAUUUUUUAUUUUCCCUGUUGCGUUGCUAUAGAUGAAGGGUGAGGACAAUCGUGUAUAUGUACUAGAACUUUUUUAUUAAAGAAACUUUUCCCAGAGGUGCCUGGGGAGUGAACUGUUUUCUAAAUAGAAGGUUUAUUGGCAUCUAACUCACAUACCAUACCAUUCACUUGUUUAACGUUUACAAUUCAAUGGUUUUUAGAAUUUUCAGAGUUCUGCAAAAAGAGUGGGCUCUGUUUACCCUGCUGGCUUCACCCAAGCUUCCUCUCAAUGGCAGGGGAUACUCAGGGUCAGCUUCCAUGCCUAAGUGGGCUCAGGGAGGGGAGACUUGCCCUCCUUUGCAAAGUCAGUUGCUCCAUGAGAGAGAACCAUUAACCUCUUACCCCAAGGCUGAGCCCCUCCACAGCCCCAGCAAGGUCUCUUCUGGAACAGCGGCUGCCCUCCCUGCAGGACAGUGUGUGACGACUUCCUCUUCUAUGCUGGAGGGGUCCCUGUUGAAAGGCAGGGGUUGGGGAACAGCCAGCUCUGCUACUUGCUAGCACAUUUUUUUUUUUUUUUUUGAGACGGAGUCUCGUUCUGUCGCCCAGGCUGGAGUGCAGUGGUGUGAUCUUGGCUCACUGCAAGCUCUGCCUCCUGGGUUCACGCCAUUCUCCUGCCUCAGCCUCCCGAGUAGCUGGGACUACAGGUGCCUGCCACUAUGCCCAGCUAAUUUUUUUUGAGUGUGUGUGUUUUUUUAGUAGAGACGGGGUUUCACUGUGUUAGCCAGGAUGUCUCGAUCUCCUGACCUCGUGAUCCGCCCACGUCGGCCUCCCAAAGUGCUAGGAUUACAGGCUUGAGCCACCGCGCCCAGCGCUGGCACAUCAUUUAACCUCCAGUUGCCUCAGAUUUUACAUUUACAAAAUGGGGAGUUUUUGUGGAGAUUAAGUGAAUUAAUAUCUGGCACAUGGUCCAUGCAAUCUGUUAGUUGGUAACAGCUACCAUUUAUUCAGUACUUUUAAAGGCCAGACAGGACUUCGAUUAUUUCCUCUAAAUCCUCACAAUCACCCUCUGAGGGGACUUUCUCCUUUAAAGAAUGGCCACAUUGUAUUUGUUUUUUUAAAUGACAUCUGGUCAUCAUCGAAAUCAAGCAAAACAAAAUUAAGAGAACCUACCCAAGAUGUCAGUGAAAUUGGAACAUUCCUGACAAUACCAGGGCAUAAAUGCAGGAAUCAGGAAUAGGCAGCAGUGAUAGAACAAUUCUGUUUGUGCCCUUGUUAACGUGAAGUUCAAAGUCAUCUUUGCAAUUAGCCAAAAGAAUCUGAAGUGAAGCUGAGGAAAUUGCUGAUGUUGAAAUAAACAUUUCCUUCCAUGA